AGCCCCGCCGCCCUCGCAAUAAGGGGCCUGAGCGCGCGGGGGAGAAGCGGGAGCGGGAGCGGGAGCGAGCUGGCGGCGCCGUCGGGCGCCGGGCCGGGCCAUGGAGCUGUGGCCGUGUCUGGCCGCGGCGCUGCUGUUGCUGCUGCUGCUGGUGCAGCUGAGCCGCGCGGCCGAGUUCUACGCCAAGGUCGCCCUGUACUGCGCGCUGUGCUUCACGGUGUCCGCCGUGGCCUCGCUCGUCUGCCUGCUGCGCCACGGCGGCCGGACGGUGGAGAACAUGAGCAUCAUCGGCUGGUUCGUGCGAAGCUUCAAGUACUUUUACGGGCUCCGCUUCGAGGUGCGGGACCCGCGCAGGCUGCAGGAGGCCCGUCCCUGUGUCAUCGUCUCCAACCACCAGAGCAUCCUGGACAUGAUGGGCCUCAUGGAGGUCCUUCCGGAGCGCUGCGUGCAGAUCGCCAAGCGGGAGCUGCUCUUCCUGGGGCCCGUGGGCCUCAUCAUGUACCUCGGGGGCGUCUUCUUCAUCAACCGGCAGCGCUCUAGCACUGCCAUGACAGUGAUGGCCGACCUGGGCGAGCGCAUGGUCAGGGAGAACCUCAAAGUGUGGAUCUAUCCCGAGGGUACUCGCAACGACAAUGGGGACCUGCUGCCUUUUAAGAAGGGCGCCUUCUACCUGGCAGUCCAGGCACAGGUGCCCAUCGUCCCCGUGGUGUACUCUUCCUUCUCCUCCUUCUACAACACCAAGAAGAAGUUCUUCACUUCAGGAACAGUCACAGUGCAGGUGCUGGAAGCCAUCCCCACCAGCGGCCUCACUGCGGCGGACGUCCCUGCGCUCGUGGACACCUGCCACCGGGCCAUGAGGACCACCUUCCUCCACAUCUCCAAGACCCCCCAGGAGAACGGGGCCACUGCGGGGUCUGGCGUGCAGCCGGCCCAGUAGCCCAGACCACGGCAGGGCAUGACCUGGGGAGGGCAGGUGGAAGCCGAUGGCUGGAGGAUGGGCAGAGGGGACUCCUCCCGGCUUCCAAAUACCACUCUGUCCGGCUCCCCCAGCUCUCACUCAGCCCGGGAAGCAGGAAGCCCCUUCUGUCACUGGCCUCAGACACAGGCCCCUGGUGUCCCCUGCAGGGGGCUCAGCUGGACCCUCCCCGGGCUCGAGGGCAGGGACUCGCGCCCACGGCACCUCUGGGAGCUGGGAUGAUAAAGAUGAGGCUUGCGGCUGUGGCCCGCUGGUGGGCUGAGCCACAAGGCCCCCGAUGGCCCAGGAGCAGAUGGGAGGACCCCGAGGCCAGACGCACACUGUCCGAGCCCUCUGCUCAGCCGCCUGGGACCCACCAGGGUGCAGCUGGGCUCCAGGGUCCAGCCCACAAGCUGCAUCAGGCUCUCUGGGAGAGGAGGGGCCUGGAGGGCCAGGAGUCCCAGACUCACGCACCCUGGGCCACAGGGAGCCGGGAAUCGGGGCCUGCUGCUCCUGCUGGCCUGGAAGACUCUGUGGGGUCAGCACUGUACUCCGUUGCUGUUUUUUUAUAAACACACUCUUGGAAGUGGC